AGUAAGGCCCCGCGGGCGUCCUGGCCGCCAUGUGCACCGUAGUGGACCCUCGCAUUGUCCGGAGAUACCUACUCAGGCGGCAGCUCGGGCAGGGGGCCUAUGGCAUUGUGUGGAAGGCAGUGGACCGGAGGACUGGUGAGGUCGUGGCCAUCAAGAAAAUCUUUGAUGCUUUUAGGGAUAAGACAGAUGCCCAGGACAUGGGCUUCCUUCUUGCUCCACCCACCCACACACCUGUGUUUCUGUCUCUUCAGAGAACAUUCCGGGAAAUCACGCUCCUCCAGGAGUUUGGGGACCAUCCCAACAUCAUCAGCCUCCUUGACGUGAUCCGGGCAGAGAACGACAGGGACAUUUACCUGGUGUUUGAGUUUAUGGACACUGACCUGAACGCAGUCAUCCGGAAGGGCGGCCUGCUGCAGGACGUCCACGUGCGCUCCAUCUUCUACCAGCUCCUGCGGGCCACCCGGUUCCUCCACUCGGGGCACGUUGUGCACCGGGACCAGAAGCCGUCCAAUGUGCUCCUGGAUGCCAACUGCACAGUGAAGCUGUGUGACUUUGGCCUGGCCCGCUCCCUGGGCGACCUCCCCGAGGGGCCUGAGGACCAGGCCGUGACAGAGUACGUGGCCACACGCUGGUACCGAGCACCGGAGGUGCUGCUCUCUUCGCACCGAUACACCCUUGGGGUGGACAUGUGGAGUCUGGGCUGUAUCCUGGGGGAGAUGCUGCGGGGGAGACCCCUGUUCCCCGGCACGUCCACCCUCCACCAGCUGGAGCUGAUCCUGGAGACCAUCCCACCGCCAUCUGAGGAGGACCUCCUGGCUCUCGGCUCAGGCUGCCGUGCCUCUGUGCUGCACCAGCUGGGGUCCCGGCCACGACAGACGCUGGAUGCCCUCCUACCGCCAGACACCUCCCCAGAGGCCUUGGACCUCCUUAGGCGACUCCUGGUGUUCGCCCCGGACAAGCGGUUAAGCGCGACCCAGGCACUGCAGCACCCCUACGUGCAGAGGUUCCACUGCCCCAGCGACGAGUGGGCACGAGAGGCAGAUGUGCGGCCCCGGGCACACGAAGGGGUCCAGCUCUCUGUGCCUGAGUACCGCAGCCGCGUCUAUCAGAUGAUCCUGGAGUGUGGAGGCAGCAGCGGCACCUCGAGAGAGAAGGGCCCGGAGGGUGUCUCCCCAAGCCAGGCACACCUGCACAAACCCAGAGCCGACCCUCAGCUGCCUUCUAGGACACCUGUGCAGGGUCCCAGACCCAGGCCCCAGAGCAGCCCAGGCCAUGACCCUGCCGAGCACGAGUCCCCCCGUGCAGCCAAGAACGUUCCCAGGCAGAACUCCGCUCCCCUGCUCCAAACUGCUCUCCUAGGGAAUGGGGAAAGGCCCCCUGGGGCGAAGGAAGCGCCCCCCUUGACACUCUCGCUGGUGAAGCCAAGCGGGAGGGGAGCUGCGCCCUCCCUGACCUCCCAGGCUGCGGCUCAGGUGGCCAACCAGGCCCUGAUCCGGGGUGACUGGAACCGGGGCGGUGGGGUGAGGGUGGCCAGCGUACAACAGGUAAGCCCGGCCCAGUCUGCCCCCGUCCCCUCAUCCUCCUUUCCCCUUUCCCCUUCCCCCCUGCUUUUCCCUCCCUUCCCCAUGCUUCCCAUUGCCCCUCCAAUGUCCAGUUCAAAUCUCUCGAGGACCUCAAGGCCUCCCCUCCACUGCACCCCCUCUGAUGGCCCCUUUAUGUGACCCUCAACUGUACACAGGUCCCUCCCCGGCUUCCUCCGGAGGCCCGGCCCGGCCGGAGGAUGUUCAGCACCUCUGCCUUGCAGGGUGCCCAGGGGGGUGCCAGGGCUUUGCUUGGAGGCUACUCCCAAGCCUACGGGACUGUCUGCCACUCGGCACUGGGCCACCUGCCCCUGCUGGAGGGGCACCAUGUGUGAGCCGCCCUACUCCCUUCACCUGGCCCUCUGUUCCUGCCCCAGCCCCUUCCCCAGACCCCUCUCCAGUCUCCUGCACCCCUUAGCCCUCCCUGCUUUGCCUGGCCCGUUGAAGUUCCAGGGAGCUUGCCCGGGUCUCCUCGGGGGAGCAGAUGAGGGCCCUGCCCCCGCCCCACUGACUUCCUCCAAUAAAGUCAUGUCUGCCCCCAA